GCAGUUGCCGAAGGGAUCUGAAGAAGUGGGAUGUGCAAAAGCGCCGGCUGGAAAUCCCGGCUGUGUCUCCGUCAACUCUUUACGCAACAGAGGUCUCCCCCUGCCCUUGGUUUCUACCGGGCCGCCUGCUCCCACUCGGCGAAAAAAAUUACACAACAGCAGCCGCGGCGAUGACGUGGAGGGCUGCCGCCUCCACGUGCGCGGCGCUCCUGAUUCUGCUGUGGGCGCUGACGACCGAAGGUGAUCUGAAAGUAGAGAUGAUGGCAGGGGGGACUCAGAUCACACCCCUGAAUGACAAUGUCACCAUAUUCUGCAAUAUCUUUUAUUCCCAACCCCUCAACAUCACGUCUAUGGGUAUCACCUGGUUUUGGAAGAGUCUGACGUUUGACAAAGAAGUCAAAGUCUUUGAAUUUUUUGGAGAUCACCAAGAGGCAUUCCGACCUGGAGCCAUUGUGUCUCCAUGGAGGCUGAAGAGUGGGGACGCCUCACUGCGGCUGCCUGGAAUCCAGCUGGAGGAAGCAGGAGAGUACCGAUGUGAGGUGGUGGUCACCCCUCUGAAGGCACAGGGAACAGUCCAGCUUGAAGUUGUGGCUUCCCCAGCCAGCAGAUUGUUGCUGGAUCAAGUGGGCAUGAAAGAGAAUGAAGACAAAUAUAUGUGUGAGUCAAGUGGGUUCUACCCAGAGGCUAUUAAUAUAACAUGGGAGAAGCAGACCCAGAAGUUUCCCCAUCCCAUAGAGAUUUCUGAGGAUGUCAUCACUGGUCCCACCAUCAAGAAUAUGGAUGGCACAUUUAAUGUCACUAGCUGCUUGAAGCUGAACUCCUCUCAGGAAGACCCUGGGACUGUCUACCAGUGUGUGGUACGGCAUGCGUCCUUGCAUACCCCCUUGAGGAGCAACUUUACCCUGACUGCUGCUCGGCACAGUCUUUCUGAAACUGAGAAGACAGAUAAUUUUUCCAUUCAUUGGUGGCCUAUUUCAUUCAUUGGUGUUGGACUGGUUUUAUUAAUUGUUUUGAUUCCUUGGAAAAAGAUAUGUAACAAAUCAUCUUCAGCCUAUACUCCUCUCAAGUGCAUUCUGAAACACUGGAACUCCUUUGACACUCAGACUCUGAAGAAAGAGCACCUCAUAUUCUUUUGCACUCGGGCAUGGCCGUCUUACCAGCUGCAGGAUGGGGAGGCUUGGCCUCCUGAGGGAAGUGUUAAUAUUAAUACUAUUCAACAACUAGAUGUUUUCUGCAGACAGGAGGGCAAAUGGUCCGAGGUUCCUUAUGUGCAAGCCUUCUUUGCCUUGCGAGACAACCCAGAUCUUUGUCAGUGUUGUAGAAUUGACCCUGCUCUCCUAACAGUUACAUCAGGCAAGUCCAUAGAUGAUAAUUCCACAAAGUCUGAGAAACAAACCCCUAGGGAACACUCGGAUGCAGUUCCGGAUGCCCCAAUCCUUCCUGUCUCCCCUAUCUGGGAACCUCCUCCAGCCACAACAUCAACAACUCCAGUUCUAUCCUCCCAACCCCCAACUUUACUGUUACCCCUACAGUAAAUGCCUGAUGGACCUGGUGCCACUAGGGUCCAAGUUCCCUUUUCAUUACAGGACCUUGGGCAAAUAAGAGGGGACCUGGGCAAGUUCUCUGAUGACCUGAUAGAUAUAUAGAGGCUUUCCAAAACCUAACUCAGGUGUUUGACCUUACUUGGGGUGAUGUUAUGUUGCUCUUAAACUCUUAACUACUACAGAGAAACAGGUAGCCCUGCAGGCAGCAGAAAAAUUCAGAGAUGAACAACAUGUCUUCUAUAGCCACUCAAUAAGGAAAGAAGGUGAGAAACAACCAGCAUUCACAUACCCAAUAGGAAGCGAGGCAGUGCCCCUUGAACAACAUAAUUCGGACCCCAGUGGUACCUUAGAUGAGUGGCAAAGAAAACAUUUUCAAAUGUGCUUAUUAGAGGGCCUACAGAGGACCAGAGCCAAGCCUCUUAAUUACCCCAAACUCUCCAUGAUAGAUCAAAAACUAGAUGAAAAUCCCUCAGCCUUUUUGGAAAGGCUGAGAGAGGCUGUAGUGAAACACACUUCCUUGUCUCCUGUUAGGUAUGUUUAUACCUCACAUAAAUAAUUCAAUUGAGGGACAGCUAAUUUUGAAAGACAAGUUUAUUACUCAGACAGCCCCUGAUAUCAGAAGGAAGCUAGAGAAACAGGCCAUGGGAUUAGAUAGCACCUUACAAAACCUCCUGAAGGUAGCCACCUCGGUCUUUUAUAAUAGGGACCAGGAGGAGGCCCAGGGGAAGGAGAGGAAACACAAGAAAAAGGCAGAGACUCUGGUGGCCACUUUGUAUAAAACCCAGUAUCCCCAAGGUACACCUGCUAGUUGCUACCAAUGUGGCAAACUAGGGCACUUCAAAAGGGACUGCCCAGGCAGCAAGAAGAAGCCACCUCAACCCUGUCCAGUAUACAAUGGGGACCACUGGAAGGCAGACUGUCCUGGGAAGCAUAGGUCACUGAGUCCAGAGCCAGUCUCACAAAUGGUCCAGCAGGACUGAUGGGUCCUGGGGCUCAACUCCCUGGCUCCAGUGGCUCAGACUGCUGUUACUACCCGGGAGCACCAGGUGAUUCUGGAGUUCGAAGGGAGGAAGGUAGACUUCUUUCUGGACACUGGAGCCAGGCUUCUGUUUUCCUCUCCAAUUCAGGCCUUCGUUCCUCCCAUAGCACAACCAUGAUGGGCAUCUCAGGAAAGACUUUAACUUGAUAUUUUUCUCAACCUAUUAGUUGCAGUCAGAGGGACCUACUGUUUACACAGGCCUUUUUAGUCAUGCCUGAAAGUCCCACUCCUUUAUUAGAUAGAGAUAUUCCAGCACGUAUGGGGGCCACCAUCCUUAUGGCUCCAGGACAAACUCCGCCUCCCCUUAGUGGAAACCAGUAUUAACCCAGAGGUUUGGGCAACUCAGGGAAGAAGUGGCCGGACUAUAACCACUAUACCAGUCUGGAUCCACCUCAAGGAUCCCACUUUUUUUCCUAACCAGAGACAAUACCCUCUGAAGCCAGAAAGUAGAAAAGGGCUAGACGCCAGCAUUGAUAACCUAAAGGCACAAGGCCUCCUUAGGCCUUGCAGUAGCCCUUGAAACACCCCAAUAUUAGGGGUGCAAAAAUCCAAUGGGGAAGGGAGACUAGUUCAGGACCUCUGCCUUAUUCAUGAGGCUGUGAUUACGAUUCAUCCAGUAGAUCCCAGUCCCUAUACUUUGCUAACUCAAAUAUCCAAGGGAACUAAAUGGUUCACAGUUCUGGGCCUAAAGGAUGCCUUUUUCUGUAUACCUUUAUACCCUGACUCCCAAUACUUGUUUACCUUUGAAGACCCCUCCAAUCAAACCACCCAGUUAACCUGGACUGUACUGCCUCAGGGAUUUAGAGAUAGCCCCCACCUAUUUGGGCAAGUAUUGUCAAGAGAUCUCUUCGAAUUCUUCCAUUCUCAGGUUAAAGUUUUACAAUAUGUAGAUGACAUUCUCCUCUGUGCCCCAACUGAGGAAGUUUCUUGAGACGGCACUGAGGCUCUCCUUAAUUUCCUAGCUGGAAAGGGAUAUAAGGCUUCAAAAUCUAAGGCUCAGCUCUAUCAGACUUUGGUAAAGUACCUAGGUCUGGUCUUGUCAGAAGGGAACAAGAGCACUAGGCGAGGAGAGGAUUAAUCCCAUUUCCUCCCUUCCUCUCCCCAGAACCCUCAAGCAGCUGAGGGAUGCUUGGGCAUUACAGGUUUUUGUAGGUUAUAGAUACCCAGGUAUGAUAAAAUAGGUUGCCCUUUAUAUCACCUUAUAAAAGAAAUUCAAGUGGCUAAAACUCACUUCCUGACCUGGGAACCUGAAGGUCAAAAGGCCAUUAAUCAGUUAAAACAAGCCUUGCUUAAAGCACCAGCCCCCAGUCUUUCUGUAGGGAAGUCCUUUAAUCUUUAUGUAUCAUAAAGGAAAGGAAUGACCCUGGGAGUUUUAAUUCAAGUUCAAGGCCCAGCUCAACAGCCAGUAGGUUACUUAAGUAGAGAGCUUGACUUGGAGGCUAAAGGAUGGCCAGCUUGCCUCUGAGCAGUUACAGUAGUGGCCCUGCUAGUCCCAGAGGCCACCAAGUUAACCCUGGGGAAUAACCUGUUUAUGCCUCACAUAAAUAAUGUGGCAGGCUUGCUGUCCUCUAAAGCGAGUCUCUGGCUAACAGACAGCUGCCUCCUCAAGUAUCAGACUUUGCUGCUAGAGGAAUCUGCAGUCCAGUUAAAAACCUGACCUUGCCUGAUCCCAGACACUUUCCUCCCAGAGGAAACUGGAGAAACUGAACAUAAUUGUGAACAGACUGUAGUACAACCUAUGCCGCUAGGGAGGAUCUCAAAGAAAUUCCCCUAGAAAAUCCAGACUGGACCCACUUUAUGGAUGGGAGCUCUUUUGUAGGACAGGGAGUCUGAAAAGUGGGAUAUGCAGUAGUCACCCUAAAUAACAUUGAAAAUGUGCCUCUCUCACCAGGCACACACACUCAAUCAGUUGAGCUGAUCCCUCUCACAAGAGCACUUGAACUAAGCAAAGGAAAGACAGCUAACAUUUAUACUGACUCCAAGUGUACCUUUCUAGUUCUCCUUGCCCAUGCUGCCAUCUGAAAGGAAAGGCACUUCCUCACCGCUAAUGGGUCUUGCAUUAAAUACCAUCAAGACAUCAACAGGCUAUUAUCCUCAGUGUUCCUCCCAUGAGAAUUAGUGGUCAGACAUUGCAGAGGGCAUCAGAAGCGGGUAGAUGAAAUAGCGAAAGGAAACAGGCUAGCAGACCAAAGAGCUAAGUCAGCAGUAAGAAGGCCCCAAGGUCCCAAAACACUUGAGGCCCCUCUGAUUUGGGAGGGCUACAUAAGGGAAAUAAAGCCUCAGUAUUCCCCUACAGAGAUAGAAUGGGCCACCUCUCGAGGUAUACUUUUCAACCCUCAGGAUGGUUACAAUCAGAAGAUUGCAAAGUACGCUUGCCAGCCUCCAGCCAAUGGAAGAUUCUUAAAAUCCUCCACUGAGCCUUUCACUUAGGAAAGCAUAAGACAUCAGUGCAUCCAAAGAUUGUUCUCAGGAGAAAAUCUACUAAAAAUGGUCAAAUAGGUUGUUAAUACUCGUGAAACCCUCUUAAAAAUAAUCCCUUUAACAGAUGACUUCUUCCCCACCACAAUCAAAGGAUGGGAAGUUACUCAGGGGAGGACUGGCAGAUAGACUUCACCCAUAUGCCCAAAAUAAAUGGCAUUCAAUGUCUUUUGGUGUGGGUGCAUACCUUCAUUAACUGGGUAGAGGCAUUCCCAUGCCCAACAGAAAAGGCCUCUGAGGUGGUGAGAAUACUAAUUAGUUAAAUAAUUCCUCACUUUGGGCUCCCUAAGUACUUCCAAAACAACAAUGGUCCCUCAUUUAAAGAAGCCUCUACCCAGUAGGGCCGAGUCUGCUAGGACUUUUUAUUGGGUUUGGUAAUACGUCACACCCUUUAGCCUCUACUGUGUCAGCCAUGUCCCAUUUAUACAAGACAAAUUGCUGGGUCUGUCCUGAGCGGUUUGCUCAGUUCAGUAACACUAAGGAACCUCUUGAUGACUUGGUAUUUACUGUCUUAGCAUUCCCUUUGUUAGCUUUACCUUUAGCCAUUAAAGACUUGUCAGGCAUAAAUGGAACAUGGUAUGGGAACACUUUCAACUGAGUAACUAACUCCUCCCAGGAAAGCAUUUCCUCCCUGGUGCCAGAAAACACUUUCCCCAAAGAUAAGCCUCACACCCUCAGGCUAGGAAAAGUUGGCCGGGUAAUAGCAAAUGCCUCCUCCUGUUUUAAAAGCAGAGGAAAAGGACCAUACCUGGGAGAUCUCAAAUAUUAUAACACCAUACUUGUAAUUGCUGAAAGCUCGGAAGUUUGGAGAAAAAGACAUAAGAAGGAUGAUCUAAGAAAAUUGGAAGCCAUAUGGAGGGGAGGCUUUCAGAAUUCAGCGUCUCCUCCUGGUUGAAAGUCCUGCUGGGAAUGGCAGGCUCUGGGUAACCACCCUGACACAUGGCACUAUAAUGUAAAAAACAACACAUAGGCCUUCCCAGACAUGCACCCUCAUGGGAUUCCAGACCCCCUGUAUGAUGCUUAGUAGUAGUGGCCUACAAAUCUGUGGGUGAACAGAACAGGAGACUUCUGGACUGACAGCCCCUGUCACAAGGGGGCAUUAUCUGAGAUAUUGGCCAGGGCAUAUCGUGUCCCUGGUCUUUUGAAACUCCAUUUGUCGGCCAGGUGUGGUGGCUUACGACUGUAAUCCCAGCACUUUGGGAGGCUGAGGCAGGUAGAUGAUGAGGUCAGGAGUUCAAGACUAGCCUGGACAAUAUGGUGAAACCCCGUCUGUACUAAUAAUACAAAAAAAAAAAAAAAAAAAGCCAGGCGUGGUGGUGCAUGCCUGUAGUCCCAGCUACUCGGGAGGCUGAGGCAGGAGAAUUGCGUGAACCCGGGAAGCAGAAGUUGCAGAAAGCCAAGAUUGUGCCACUGCACUCUAGCCUGGGCAACAGAGUAAGUCUCCAUCUCAAAAAACAAACAAACAAACAAAACUCAAUUUAUCAGGUGGACCUUUCUCAUUUAGCAUGUAAAAUUCCAAAUGGCAUCGUGAGUGACUAUCCUGAGUAUAGAUAUCCCCAUCCCAAAGAUGUUCCUAUUACAUGCAGGAGGGGGAAGCUUCUAAGAUAUGAGAAAGAUCUGCCUGUGUCUCUCACAAGCUACAACUUAGAACUGGCCCUUCAGGGGACAGGGCUUUAUUUCCUUUGUGGCUCCUGGCUACACUUAAUCCUCCCUAGGCACUGGAAGGGAACCUGCACUAUCGUGGCAGUGGUUCCUGACCUGUUAUCUUUAAAUUCCACUGAUAUGGCAGCAUCAUCUGGGGACAUCCCUAGCCUAGCGUCUUUUCUAGUGAGUGUGCUAUCUCAGAUGCGCUGAACAAAGAGGUCUAUCAUUUCCAUGCCCUCAUAUGGAGACUUAACUGAAAGAGAAGAUUGGGUAGGACCUGCACAUGACAAUCCUAUCUCAGAAAAACCAUGGAUAGGGGAUUCUAUAGUCAGAGGCCUAUUCUGGUUUGCUGGUAUUCCUCUCCUUGAAAAAUCAGUACUUAAUAUUUCUAUUAUGAUGCCACAAGGGUAGAAGCUAACAGUAGGAGCCAUAGAAGCACAACAACAAUUCAUAAACUCUUUAGCCUCAGUAGUUAUGCAAAAUAGACAGGCCCUAGAUAUCCUUAUGGCCAAAGUAGGGGGUACCUGUGCACUUUUAAAAAGAAGCAUGUCACUUCUAGAUCAAUACCUCUAGUCAAGUAGAAGAGAAUGUACAGGUGCUUAAAGAUCAAAUUAGAACAUUGACAGAUUAAGAGAGAAUGCGGGCUCCAGUCCCAGUUGGCUACAAUCCCUCUUAAAUGGAUUCCAGUCUUCUUUGUGGAACUGGUUAGCUCCUUUAUUAGGCCCCCUUUUGCUCGUGUGUUUUGUACUAAUGUUUGGACUUUGUAUAUUCAAUACUGUAACUCAAAUUGUUUCCUCUCACUUAGAGGCUAUUAAACUCCAAAUGGUGCUGCAGAUAGAACCACACAUAGACACGCCAUUCUUCUGGGGACCCUUAGACCAAUCUCAGGAGGAGCCCUAACUGCUGUAACCCCAACGACGCCCCCUUCCAGCAGGAAGCAGCCAGGAGUGGUCAUCGUCCACUUUCCCCAACAGCAGUUGGGGUCUCCACUCCUGAAGCAGGGAAUGAGAAAGGAGGAAGGAAGAAACCAGUCAGACAGGCAGUUAGGGUGGGUCCUCGGUAAAAUUCUUCCAAACAAAAGAACAGCUUGAAAAAUCAAACUGCAGGCACAGAGAAGAGAACUUGUACAGGGAGGCUUGCCUUAGACAUGUCCACAGCUGCCUAGGUAAGAAAGACUACACAGGAGACUUGCCCAGAGAUGCCCACAAUGGAAAAUUCCAUUCCCUGAGACAUGCGCAGUAAGGGGAACAAAGCCAUAUGGAGUAACUCAAGCUAAGGGCCUGCAUGCACACUGGGAGGAUAGGGUAGAACUACCAGAAAUUCAUGCUUUAUGCAAAUGAGAUGCCCAGCACUCAUCAAUUUCUUACAAAAGCCUCUGUAUUCAACUGUGAAAUGGCGACACUCUUUUGGGCCCCCUCUUGGCAGUGGGGAGCUUUCUUUUUUCACUUUUUAAAUUUUUGCUCCAACCUCACCUUUGGGGUCCAUGCUCCUUAAUUUUCUUGGUUAUGAGACAAAGAACUUCAGGUGAUACCUUGGGCAAUGAGAGACUGCUACAUUGUGGUGCAUUGGUGAGACUGUAAAACUAUCAGUUUAUUGCUGAUAACCCCAACAUCAGCAAUGAUGCUUAUGGAAAAAGAAAACAAACCCUUUAUGAUCAGCUGGAUCCUUUAGUUGUUUGCAAAGAUGACUCCAAUCCUACACCCUUCCCUGAAUCCAUGUCCAUUGCUGUGUAACUUUGUAGUGCCUCUAACUGUGUGACCUCUUUCAGCCAACUUAAGAAGACAGCAGUGAAGGCGUGCCAGUUCCAAGUGUAAGCCCCAAGAGGUCUUGUGUGUCUUCAUUUGCUUCCUCGUGUGCUUCUAAUGGUGCUGGGAGAAGAACAGGUCGAGACUAGCCUGCUGGAGGAUGAGAGAUGCUGGCUACCACAUCCUUGUUGCUCCAGUGGAGGCCAGGCUAGAUUAGAUGACAGCCACCUGACUCCAUUCAGCCUGCAUGGUGGUCUGAGGCCUUCCCCCCUACAGCCUCUCCCCUUUAUCUUUCACGGUAAUCACCCCUCAUUACUCGUACUUCUAACUCCAUCUUGAAAGCUGCUUCCUGGAAGAUCCAAACGGACACAAGGAGGGACUGAAGGAUUAGAAUGAGGGAAGUAACCCAUGCACUGCUUAUUUGAGAUGGGGAACCGAAGGACUUUGGCAGUUCCUACACAGAGACAGAUGGCAGAGAUGACAAGGUUUCUCAGAGAAUGCGUGAGUAACUGGAAUGGCUUUUCCUGAUGACCCAGACAGCCUGCUCAAGAGCACACUGUUGCAGCUGCCCUCCUUGGAUGGAACUAUGGAAUGAUUUUUAUUCUUCUACUUCCCAGGUGAAUGGGAAACCAAGGACACAGUCAGCAUUUAACAAAAAGGAAUCUGCAUCUCAGUCAGAACUGUAUUGCAUUUGCUUCUCUCUGGAUUACCUUGAAGUUACUCCCCUUCCCUCAAUAAUAAUGGCAUUAUGAAAAAAAUUGGAAUUGAUCAAAUGAAGUAAAGAGUAAACAGAGGAAAGACUA